GCAAGACUCCGUCUUAAAACAACAAUAACAACAACAAAAAACAGAUACUCGUGCAGGAAUAGUCAGAGCUAAUGAAAAACACAGACUAGAAAGUCCAAAAUUAGGCCCCAGUGUAUGUGAUCAUUUAGAAUAUAACAAAGAGAAUGAUUUAAUUCCUUCUACAAUAGUUAUCUUGGACAAAGGCAAGAUAACUUAGAACACCAUUUGGUGAAUUUGGAGCUUUGAAGGGAAGCGUUUGUCCUUUGUGUGGUGGUGGGCAGCUAGGCUAUCCUUUGGUAAUCACAGACUUUAAUCCAGUAUAUAAGGGUUUCUCUUUCCACGAGUAGAGGUGCUGCAAAACACUUUUUAAGCUUGGUGCACUAUUCAAAUAAACCUGGAGAGGUAAGACUAUGGCCUGCAUCUAUGUAUGGGCCUUUGAUGGAGCUUCCAAAUUCUUUCAGGUUGCUUUCUUGACUGGCUUCUCUUGCAGCCUAUGCUGUAAUAUCCUGAGGUUGUCCAAGAAUGGAGUAAAGAUGAAAUUGCCAAUGGGAAGCAGGGAAGGAAUGCGCGGCAUUUCCUUCAAUAUAGACCCAUCAUCUAACCACUGUCUCCACUGCCUCUACCACCACCCUACUCCAAUCACCAUCCUCUCCCACUUACAUUAUUACAACUGCCCAUUAACUAGUCUCCCUGCUUUUGCUCCAAACCCUACAAUCUAUUUUAAAUACAGCAACCAGAGUGAUCUUUUUCAAUACUUAUGACAGUUCUUGUUACUCUUCAACUCAAAUCCUCAUAUAGCUUUUCAUCUUACCAUAAUAAAAUACAAAAUCCUCACAGAGUUCUACAAGAUAGCACAUGAUUUGGCCCUGAAAUACCUCUCUGACCUCACAUCCUACCAUUAUUUAUUUCUCUCAGUGUACUCCAGGCACAUAAUUUUCCUUGCUAUUCUGCAAACAUACCAAGUAUACUCUCACUGCCCCCCAUCCCAGCUUUUUUUUUUUUUUCCAUUUGCUGUUUCCUUUGCCUGUAUGCAUUUUCUCCAGAUUCCCGCAUGGCUCACACUCACACUCCCUUAUGUCCUUCAUUUCUUUGCCCAGAUUCCACCUUAUCAUCUGAUAAGGUCCUGAUCUUCUUUUUCCUCCCACCGCUGUCAUUCUCUGUCUGGGGUUCUGUCUUAUGCCUUCAAUAUGAAUAUUAACAAAGAGUCAAUGAAUGAACAAAGAGUCCAAUGUAUUAGGAUAAUUUGCUGGCUGUAUUUUUCUUUGUGGUGCUAGCUUGGGUCCCAUCCCUCCUUCUUGACUCAGUGUCUUCGUCCAUUUUGUGCUGCUAUAAUAAAAUACCUGAAAAUGGGCAAUUUAAAAACAACAGAAAUGUAUUUCUCACAGGUCUAGAGGCUAGGAAGUCUAAGAUCAAGGCAUCAGCAUCUGGUGUCUGCUUCCACGAUGAUGCCUUGAAGUCUGCCUCCUCUGGAGAGAAGGAACAGUAUGUACUCACAUGGCCAAGUCAGAAGGGCAAAAAAGGGAUGAACUUUCUCCAUCAAGCCCUUUAAAUGCACAGCUAAUGGGCAGCUAAUGCCAUUUGGAAGGGGAGGAGCCCUCAUAACCAAAUUACCUCUUAAAGGCCCACCUCUUAAUACUAUCAUAUUGGCAACACCUGAAGUUUGAAGGGGACACAUUCAAACCGUAGCAUUCAGCAUGGUAGGGCAAUGUCCUCAAUUUACAAAGCAUGAGUACAAAUACAGACUGUGUGCAAUUUUCUGGUGCAUUUCUCAAACUCCUUUGAUUUGGUCCCUUAUAUAUAAUACACAGCUACCCCUUCCCAACCACUGCUUCUCUCAAUUUGAAGAUUUUUUAGAAUUGUUUGGUGAAACUUCUUUCCCUGGUACCUUGAAUUUUGGUCUGUAAUAUGGUUUGGCUGUGCCCCCACCCAAAAUUUCAUCUUGAAUUGUAAUAAUCCCCACAUUUCAAGGGCGAGACUAGGUGGACAUAAUUGAAUCAUGGGGGCAGUUUCCCCCAUGUGUUCUUGUGAUAGUGAAUUCUCACAAGAUCUGAUGAUUCUACAAGGGGCUUCCCCCUUCACUCAGCUCUCAUUCUGUCUCUUGCUGCCAUGUGAAGAAGGUUGGUUUGCUUCCCCUUCUGCUGUAAUUAUAAGUUUCCUGAGGCCUUCCCAGCCAUAUGAAACUGUGAGUCAAUUAAACCUCUUUCCUUUAUAAAUUAUCCAGUCUCGGGCAUGUGUUUAUUAGCAAUGUGAGAACAGACUCUGGUUUGUGUUAAUGGGCUUUUUUCUCAAUCUGAUGUUGUCUGUGUCAUAUUUAAAGACUUCUCUCAAUAUUUCUGGCAAUCAUUGCUCUUUUUGUAGCACUGCUAUAUUCUUUUCUUGUUUUCAUAUUUCUGUAGUCAUUCUAGUGAGAUUUGGGGAGGGAAGAUAGGUAAAUACAUGGACUCAAAUCAUCAUCUUUUUUCUUAACAUUUUAAUUUAUGUAUAUGCCAGCACAUGUACAUAAUUUAGCAUAAAUGAAUAAAAAUGAGCAUAUAAAUGCCUUUAAAAUAAAAAUUUAAGUAGAAUUUCAUUGAAGUAUAGCAUACAUCCAGAAAUCACACACAUCAUAGGUAUCUAAUUUUAUUUUCAAAUUGAACAUAACCAGCACCUAGAUCAAAUAAUACAUUGUUAUGAACACUCUAUAAGCCCCUCUUUUUGCCUCCUCUUAGUUGCUCUUCCCUGAAAGGUAACCAAUAUCCUAACUUCUAACACUACAGUUUGUUUUAAAAUCUUACAUGAAUUGAGUCAUACUCAUUAUGAGUAUUACUCAUUGUGUGUCUCUUCUUUUGUUCAACAUUUGUUUACGUGAAACUCACUUAUGUUGCAAAUAACAGUAGUUGUUUCUUUCUCAUUCCACUUUUAGGUAGAAACCCCAAAGAAAUUUGUAGCUAUGACCUGUAUGACAAAAUGUUCAGAGAAGCACUAUUUAACCCCCAACUGGAAACAGUCAAAAUGUGUACCCAUAGUAGAAAUAAUAAAUAAAUGUCUAUACAUUCAUACUAGGCAAUUCUAAACAUGCUUUUUUAAAAGUAUCAUUUUUUCUUUUCCAUUUUUGCCUAGAUCUCUCCCAUCCAGCUUUACAUUUGUAUUCUGGCCACAAAGGCUUUCACCUGCAUCUAAGGAAACUCAUAUUAACAACUUAGUAUAUAUCUUUCCAUAUUUUCUCCUGACAAUAAUUAUACAUAUACAUGCAUUUACAUAUAUACACAUGUAUACACACAUGCCUAUGGGGGAGUUGUUAUUGUAAAGAAAGGGAUUAUACUGUAUACCAUUUUCUAAAUCUCGCUUUGUCAGUUCAUUAUAUUAAAGGCAGGAUUCUUAUAUUUUUUAGAUAGUAUGUAUCUGGAAUAAUAUACAGAAAAUAUUACAAAUUAUGAAAGUUGGAUUAAGUUUCAUCCAACUGAAGUAUUAGUUGGUUCAUAUUCUCUAGAAUGAAGGAGAAGUUGGAGUAUUUAUUUUAAUAAACACUUAUUACUAUGCCAAAAAUGUUGCUAAGCCCUAAGGAUUCUUCUCUUUGCAGUCUAGGUAUACUUAGAGAACUGUGUUCACGUUUAGACACCGCAGUGUAAUACAAAGGACAACUAGAGCCUGUUCAAAGGAGAGAAACAUGAGUAUAUAGUGAGAGAACUAACAACUUGAACUGGGAGUAAGAUAAGAGUGUAGAUGAGAGAUGACCAUUUUCUUCAAGUAUUGAAGGCUCAUCGUGUGGAAAAAAAGUUAUACCGAGGAGUUAUAAUAUUAUGAUCACUGUUUUUAAUGGAAGAUGAUUGAAAGUGAAAACCUAAACCAAGAAGAAAUAAUUAAAGAACUGUGUUUGUGCAAUGGCUUAUCUUAUGAGAUGGUUGGACAAGAAGGAUCAGAUACAUCAAAGUUGGAGAUGUUUUUCUUAGGGUAUCCUCGUAUAGUUGGAUUAUCAUUAUUUCCUAAUUUAACGAGUCUUACCAUUGUUGCUCAAGAUAUAAAAGAAAUUUCAGGGUUAGAGCCUUGUUUACAACUUAAAGAACUUUGGAUUGCUGAGUGCUGCAUAGAGAAAAUUGAAGGUCUUCAAGAAUGUAGAAAUUUGGAAAAACUAUAUUUAUAUUUUAAUAAAAUUUCCAAAAUAGAAAAUUUAGAGAAAUUAAUCAAAUUGAAGGUUCUUUGGCUGAACCACAAUACAAUUAAAAAUAUUGAGGGUUUGCAAACUUUGAAGAAUUUAAAAGAUCUCAACCUUGCUGGAAAUCUAAUAAAUAGCAUUGGUCGAUGUCUUGACUCCAAUGAACAACUGGAAAGAUUAAACCUUUCUGGUAACCAAAUAUGUUCUUUCAAGGAACUCACGAACUUAACCAGGCUGCCUUGCUUAAAGGAUUUAUGUCUGAAUGACCCUCAAUAUACAACCAAUCCAGUUUGUCUUCUGUGUAAUUAUUCCACACAUGUAUUAUAUCAUUUGCCUUGCCUUCAAAGAUUUGACACAUUGGAUGUGUCAGCAAAGCAAAUCAAGGAACUGGCAGAUACCACAGCAAUGAAAAAAAUAAUGUAUUAUAAUAUGCGUAUAAAAACUCUUCAGAGGCAUCUUAAAGAAGACCUUGAAAAACUGAAUGAUCAAAAAUGCAAAUUACAAAAGUUGCCAGAAGAACGAGUAAAAUUAUUCAGCUUUGUGAAGAAAACUUUGGAACGAGAACUGGCUGAACUCAAGGGCUCGGGCAAAGGGCACAGUGAUGGAUCCAAUAACAGUAAAGUAACUGAUCCUGAAACACUGAAGAGUUGUGAAACUGUCACUGAAGAACCAAGUCUUCAACAGAAGAUAUUGGCCAAACUAAAUGCCUUGAAUGAAAGGGUAACAUUCUGGAACAAAAAACUAGAUGAAAUUGAAGCAAUUUAUCAUAUUGAAGUAAAACAAAAGAAGAAAAGUCAUGGCUUAUUGAUCCCACUUUUGUUAAUUGAGUUAGAGACUGUGGGAAAUUUCCAUUUUGAAGAAGGCACUCGAUCUGAUGACUGGUUUAAUUUCUGCUAUGAAUUAAUUCUGUCACGUUUUUGUGCCUGGGACUUCAGAACAUACGGUAUUACAGGAGUAAAAGUAAAACGCAUCAUUAAAGUUAACAACCGUAUUCUGAGACUAAAAUUCGAAGAGAAAUUUCAAAAGUUUUUGGAGAAUGAAGAUAUGCAUGAUUCAGAGAGCUACCGAAGGAUGCUGGAAUGCCUUUUUUAUGUUUUUGAUCCUGAAGUUUCAGUGAAGAAAAAGCAUCUUCUACAAAUACUUGAAAAAGGAUUCAAAGACAGUGAAACAAGCAAGCUGCCUCUCAAAAAAGAAGCCAUCAUUGUUUCUAACAGUCUAAGUAUAAGUGAGUGUCCCAGAAUUGAAUUUUUACAGCAAAAGCACAAAGAUGAGAAGAAAAUCUCUCUUAAGCAUGAGCUCUUCAGACAUGGCAUCCUCCUCAUUACAAAAGUUUUCCUUGGCCAGAGUGUUCAGGCCCAUGAAAAAGAAUCCAUCAGUCAAUCCAACUAUCCAAUGGUUAAUUCAGUGUUCAUUCCUCGGAAAUAUUUACUAAAUUCUGUCAUGGGACAAAGAAACUGUGAUUGCAGUGUUCGGCAGUGCAAGUGGUUUGUCUUUGAUCAUGACCUUGUUUUGCCGGAAUAUGUUGUUGAAUUUGAGUAUAUUACAAUGGUCAAGGCACCCUCUUUAUUUUCUGUAUUCAACAAUGUUAUUCUAGAAGAAAGCAAAAAAAACCCAGAAGUAUCAGUAUUUUCCAAGGAUUUGAAAUUUGAUGAUGAAGUUAUAAAAAUGGAGCCCAGAAUCAAGGCCCGACCAAAACUGAUUAGUUUGGAUGAUAAAACAAUACUUUCCCUUGCAAAGACUAGCGUUUACAGUCAUAUUGUGAGUCUGAAUCUACAUGGAAACAGCUUGAGUAAAUUGAGAGAUCUCUCCAAGUUAACAGGACUUCGAAAACUAAACAUUAGCUUUAAUGAAUUUACCUGUUUAGAUGAUGUAUACCACUUGUAUAACCUUGAAUAUUUGGAUGCAAGCCAUAACCAUGUGAUAACCCUUGAGGGAUUUAGAGGUCUGAUGAAACUGAAGCACUUAGACUUGAGCUGGAAUCAACUGAAAAAAUCUGGCAAUGAAAUAAAUAUGUUAUGCAAACACACCACAAGCCUUCUCACUCUUGAUAUUCAACAUAAUCCAUGGCAAAAGCCAGCCACAUUGAGGCUGAGUGUUAUUGGCAGAUUAAAGACUCUUACCCAUUUAAAUGGAGUCUUCAUUUCUGAAGAAGAAGCAACAGCAGCUAUGAAAUUUAUUGCAGGAACAAGGAUUACUCAGUUAUCUCUCUUACGGCAUUCUAGUACUAAAGAGGAGAGACCACGGAUACUUAGUAUAUGGCCUUCUGCCAAAAUUCUGACGCAGGUUUCAAAGUUAGGACCUCAUUUACAUCUGAGUGGAAACUGCUACUUGAAGAUAACUGCCUUAAAUUUAGAUGGACAACAUCUUUUUGAAAUCACAAAUUUAGAAAAAUUGGAAAAUUUGAAAUGGGCAUCAUUCAGCAAUAAUAAUCUCACUAAAAUGGAGGGUCUGGAAUCCUGUAUUAACUUGGAAGAGCUCACAUUAGAUGGAAACUGCAUCUCAAAGAUAGAAGGUAUUUCCAAGAUGACUAAAUUAACUCGCCUCAGCAUAAAUAAUAAUCUUCUCACUGGUUGGGAAGAGCAUACCUUUGAUAACAUGCUUCAUCUUCACUCGCUUUCUCUUGAGAACAACAGAAUCACUUCAUUGAGUGGUUUACAAAAAUCUUUUACUCUUGUUGAGUUAUACAUAAGCAAUAACUAUAUUGCUGUCAAUCAGGAGAUGCACAAUUUAAAGGGUUUAUGCAACUUGGUCAUUCUAGACAUGUGUGGGAACAUCAUUAUAUGGAAUCAAGAAAACUACCGGUUGUUUGUAAUAUUUCAUCUUCCAGAACUGAAAGCUUUGGAUGGGAUACCAAUUGAACCAUCAGAGACUGACAGUGCAAAAGAUUUGUUUGGUGGUAGACUUACUUCUGACAUGAUUGCAGAACGACAAGGACAUUCCAACUUCAAACAAAUGCAAGAACUAAAUUGGACUUCAUCAUCUAUUAGAACAGUGGAUUUGAUUCCAGUCGACCAAUUUAGAAAUGUGUGUAAUGUGAAUCUACAGAACAAUCAUCUUACCUCAUUCAGUGGAUUAAUCUAUCUACCUAAUGUGAAGGUCUUAUGCCUUAACUAUAAUCAUAUUGAAUCAAUCAUGCCCAGACUAAAGCCUCAGACUCACUUAACCAGUAGACAACUACUGUACCAGAAAGUGCCUUCAAGUGGCUAUGGACAGCAAGGAAUUUCAAAAACAAACAGAGAUAUAAUGAGCAGUGAAAAUUUGCCUCCAAUAAUGCACAGUUUAGAAGUUCUUCAUUUGGGCUACAAUGGAAUUUGUAAUUUGAUCCAGCUACAACUUAACAGACUAAGAAAUUUAAAAUUCCUCUUUCUACAGGGUAAUGAAAUCAGCCAAGUUGAAGGGCUUGACAACUUAGUAGUCCUUCAAGAAUUGGUAGUGGACCAUAACCGCAUCCGAUCAUUUAAUGACAGUGCUUUUGCCAAACCAAGUUCUUUAUUGGCACUUCACUUGGAGGAAAACAGACUACGAGAACUGGGCAAAUUACAAUCUUUGGUAAAACUAGAGAAACUCUUCCUAGGAUAUAAUAAAAUCCAGGAUAUCACAGAACUGGAAAAACUUGACGUUAUCUCUACUCUCAGGGAGCUUACAGUGUAUGGCAAUCCAAUUUGUAGAAAAAUGCUACAUCGCCACAUGCUUAUAUUUCGACUGCCUAACUUACAGAUGUUAGAUGGAAGUCCUGUGAAUUCAGAUGAUAGGGCAAAAGCUGAAUUUCACCUCGCUGAACUACAAGCAAAGAAAAACUCGCUUAUUCCUGUUACCCACUCUCCUAUGGAUGGCAGAUCAUUUGGCCAAGUGAAAACUCCUCCCAUAGAGAUAACAAAUGUACUUCUGCCUAGUGGAUUCAGCCAUUACUUGGGAUCUGACGUCACUUUAACUCCUGAAGUUGAAGACAAAAAAAACAAGAAUGCUGGGAUUCUGACAAAUAAUCCUCGGAGCAUCCAUGCAGAAAUAGCUUUUCGGCAACUCAGAGGGAUAAGUAUCUCUCCAUCUCUUUUAUCACAUCAGAAUAUUGCAUCUCCUACUGCACAAAUAUACCAGAGCAACCAAGAUAAGAGAAGAAUUUUUGGGAGCAACUUUCCAAGAUCAAAUCGAAUGUAACUGCCUAAAGAGAAAUGAGCAUACACCAAGAAACUCACCUGUUUAGUAGUUGUACAAAAACUAGCGGACAGUGGUCAGUUAAAAAAAAAAAAAAAAGAUAAUCAUGUUACUUAAGUUACUGAAGCACUUCAGUUCCAUAUGAAGAUAAUCUAUUACCCUUCAUGAACUUGAUUUAAUAUCACCUCUCUUAAACUUUCUUUAUGGUUAUCUUUAGUUAUUUGUUUGAAUUUCUAUAUCAUAAAAAUCAUCAACUAUUACAUCAGACUACAAUUUGAAAAGACAAAAGUGACAUGAAACAAAGUCCAGAGAACUGAAUGCUUAGUUCUAGUAUUAGAAACAUUUAGUCAUGAAAUGUCAUUAUGAAAAGUCAUAGGAAGAUAUUGAGAAAAGAUAACUUUAGGAAAUAGGCAUACUUUCAUUUGUAGAGUAUCUAUUCAUUUGAGAUUACACAAAACUACAGCACAUUUCUUACCAAACACAACUAUUACUAAAGCAAGAUGAGUUUUGCUAGUUGAACUACAGAUUGGUUUUUAGGACUGUAUUUUUUUAAAAAAUACCCUCAAACCAGAUCGGCCCUCAAAAUUGUUUAGAGAUGCAAAUUGUGGGCAUCAAUAGUAGUUUCUAAAUGUGGCUAACCGUGGGUGCAACCAGUCCUUCAUGCUCUAAGAAUAAAAAAAGCGUCCGAUUUCAAAUACAAAUCAUUUAAUUACACCUACAGUGAUACAAGUUUACAAGUAGUUUCAGGCUGAAGAGAACAUGUAUUCAAACUGAGUGGACACAUUUAAAAAUAUGACCUUCAAUAAUUAUACUUCACUGAACUUUUCUAAACUAUUACAUUGCAUAGUACUAGGACGUAUCACAGAUUAAUCAAAUGUGGUUAUGAAUUUGCUUGUUACAGUUACUAAAAUUGAUAACCAAAUUGCCAAUCAUAUUUUGAUAUAAAUGAGCUCCAUCAUUCAUGAAGUAUUCUAUUCAAAAUUUUAAAGUUAUUGGCUCAACAGUACACAUAGUUUCAUAAUAUUUUAUACUUUCCUUACACGAAAAUAAAUUAUUUUAACUAAAAUAUGUAGACUUUAUAAUCUGUCUGGAAAUAGUUUUAAAGGUACUUUGGAAAUGAUAUAAUUCCAAUGUCUAUGCAACAAUUUUGUAUUUUUCUUUUUAAAUGCUGUAUGUCUUUACUUUAAUCAUGUAAUAUUUAAAAGUUCAAACCUAAUUACAGAUUGAUUUUGCUCUUUGUAAUGUGUGGUUUUUAAACAACUAUUACAUUUAGGUGGAAAUAGGAUCUUUUGUUUAAAAACAACUAUGCAGUUCUUAAGAUGUCCAGAAGAUGUCUUUGUUGCCCUUUAGUUUUGACAACUGCUUUCAUUAUAGUGUUGUGACAGUCUACUCUUCACUAUUUAUUACUAAAUUGGCAUCAUCUUCUUUUUUUCUUUUAUGAUUAUGUAUAAAUUAAAUGCUGAAUAUAUGUUACUUUUAUAAUAAAAAGUGUCUUAAAAUAACAAAGUGGGAAAAUAAAUGUAAUAGGUUUCACUGGAGAAAAAUGUUCAGAAUAGAAAUAUAUAAAGCAGAAAAAACAUAACUUACACUGUAUUCACUUAGCAUUUUGGCAUAUUUUCUUUUAGCCAUUUUUCCUAUGGACUUUUAAUACAUUUGAGAUCUUCAUGUGAUUUUUAUGUACACAUUGUUAAAUUUUGAGCUAUUUAUAAUUCUUAAAAAUUGUUAAUUAAAUGUCAUCUGAGCCGGGCGCAGUGGCUCACAUCUGUAAUCCCAGCACUUUGGGAGGCCAAGGCAGGCAGAUCACAAGGUCAGAAGUUCGAGACCAGCCUGGCCAAUAUGGUGAAACCCCAUCUCUACUAAAAAUACAAAAAUUAGCCAGGCGUGGUGGUGUGCUCCUGUAGUCCCAGCUACUAGGGAGGCUGAGGCAGACAAAUUGAGCAAGACUCCAUCUCAAAAAAAAAUUUUUUUUUCAUCUAAAUUUCUGAGUAGCUGGAAUUACACCACCACGCCAGGUGCAGUGGUUCACGCCUGUAAUCCCAGAACUUUAGGCGGCCAAGGUGGGCAGAUCACCUGAGGUCAGGAGUUCAAGACCAGCCUGGCCAACAAGGCAAAGCCCCAUCCCUACUAAAAAUACAAAAAUUAACUGGGAAUGGUGGCGUACACCUGUAAUCUCAGCUACUCAGGAGGCUAAGGCAGGAGAAUCGCUUGAACCAGGGAGGCAGAGGUUGCAGUGAGCUGAGAUGGCACCACUGCACUCCAGCCUGGGUGACAGAGUGAGACUCCCUCUCAAAAAAAAAAAAAAAAAAACUGUAAAAGAGAGUAAACUAUUUAUUCAUCAAGGUAUUUCACUUAGAUAAAAUGUAUAAUUUAUCCAGUAAAGUUAUUAUGUCUUUGCUCCCAGCAAAUGUCUUGAUUUAUUUUGCAAGCAAAUGUAUGAUUAUAUAACUUGUUUUCAUUAAAGACAAUUCCACAAACAACCUGGUAAGCUAGAAAUUAAGGCACUUUAUAGAUUAGAAGCCUCCAAAGCUGAACCGAAUACAGGCAGUGUGAAAUUAGUCUGAUUUCUAUAUAUAAAAUUAACUGCGAUUAAUUGUCCAAUACAAACUUUACUAUUUACUUCCAUUUUUAAAAAAAUUUUUGUAGAGAUGGAGUCUCACUAUAUUGCCCAGGCUGGUCUCAAACUCCUGGCUUCAUGUAAUCCUCCUGCCUCGGCUCCCGCAACGUGCUGGGAUUAUAGGCAUGAGCCACCAUGCCUGGCCAUUUACUUCUAAUUUUUCUAGUCUUAGAUUUUUCUGACUAUUGACACAAAAUUAACUGAUUGUGAAUAUAUUUUUGCCUAGAAUAUCUAGUGUGCACUAUGUAUGUGUGUUUGCAGGCACUCCUGACUAGUUUACAAAUAACCCUUAUAUUUAAGUAACAUGCCAUUUCACUCUUCAUAAGCUAUCUUACAUUAUGAAAAGUGUUUAAUGUUUUAAAACAUUAGAUCUCACUCUUAGUCAUGCUCUAGGCUCUUGGCUUCAAUUAAAUAUUACUUACAUAAAGGGAGGUAAGAUUAUUAUAAUAUUCUAUUAGUAGAAGCAAGCACUUACGGCCAAAUUCCUUUGGUUAUUCAGUGAAGCUAACCAAAUCAUUUUGGUUAUGGGCUAGAAACCGGCUGGUUUUUCUGAUGCCUUACUAUAAAACUUAGAGCUUCUGGACCACCUGCAAGUGCUAACUAUGUGUUCAUUUUUCUACAUUUUCCUCCCUUCUCCAUUAUUGAAGUAUUUUUGAAGAAAAACCUACGCUGAACUGCAAUUUAAAUUCUCAGUUGCCUUUUAGAACUAGGUCAGUAAGAAAUACCACAGCUAUUUUAUUAGUAAUAUUAUUUCUGCAAGUUUUUACUUUACAAAUAUGUAAAUUAUACCAUUCUACUGUUACUGUUUUUCUUUCCAUUGUGAAUAAAAUUGUUUUGUAAACUA